GCAGCGGCCUGGGCUGGGAUGUGAGGAGCGGCGGGUUCCGGGCUCCGGGCUCUGGGUGGCGGCGGCUGUGAGCGGCGGCACUGCGGCGCAGGCCAGCGGGCGCCGUCGGCGGCUGGCCCUGUCGGCCGCGGGAUGAGGAAGCGGACCGAGCCCGUCGCCUUGGAGCAUGAGCGCUGCGCCGCCGCGGGCUCGUCCUCCUCCGGCUCGGCCGCCGCGGCGCUGGACGCCGACUGCCGCCUGAAGCAGAACCUACGCCUGACGGGCCCGGCGGCGGCUGAGCCGCGCUGCGCAGCCGACGCGGGAAUGAAGCGGGCGCUGGGCAGGCGAAAGGGCGUGUGGUUGCGCCUGAGGAAGAUACUUUUCUGUGUUUUGGGGUUGUACAUUGCCAUUCCAUUUCUCAUCAAACUAUGUCCUGGAAUACAGGCCAAACUGAUUUUCUUGAAUUUCGUAAGAGUUCCCUAUUUCAUUGAUUUGAAAAAACCACAGGAUCAAGGUUUGAAUCACACGUGUAACUACUACCUGCAGCCAGAGGAAGACGUGACCAUUGGAGUCUGGCACACCGUCCCUGCAGUCUGGUGGAAGAACGCCCAAGGCAAAGACCAGAUGUGGUAUGAGGAUGCCUUGGCUUCCAGCCACCCUAUCAUUCUGUACCUGCAUGGGAACGCAGGUACCAGAGGAGGCGACCACCGCGUGGAGCUUUACAAGGUGCUGAGUUCCCUUGGUUACCAUGUGGUCACCUUUGACUACAGAGGUUGGGGUGACUCAGUGGGAACGCCAUCUGAGCGGGGCAUGACCUAUGACGCACUCCACGUUUUUGACUGGAUCAAAGCAAGAAGUGGUGACAACCCCGUGUACAUCUGGGGCCACUCUCUGGGCACUGGCGUGGCGACAAAUCUGGUGCGGCGCCUCUGUGAGCGAGAGACGCCUCCAGAUGCCCUUAUAUUGGAAUCUCCAUUCACUAAUAUCCGCGAAGAAGCUAAGAGCCAUCCAUUUUCAGUGAUAUAUCGAUACUUCCCUGGGUUUGACUGGUUCUUCCUUGAUCCUAUUACAAGUAGUGGAAUUAAAUUUGCAAAUGAUGAAAACGUGAAGCACAUCUCCUGUCCCCUGCUCAUCCUGCACGCUGAGGACGACCCGGUGGUGCCCUUCCAGCUUGGCAGAAAGGUGGGUCCUGGCCUCUGCCUCUGGUGUAGCUGGCAUCUUGCACACUCAGCCAGUGUGGGUGGACCAGGCUGGGAGUGGGCAGGCGGGAAGGCAGCCCCUGCAUGCUGCAUCACGGGCUGCGCACCAGCCACGUCAGGCUCAGGAGGCCACCUCAUCCUCCCUGCGUCACCUCCAGGCUGCUUCGGAAGGACAUGGGAGGUCUGGUGUAAAGGUUGGGGCAGGGGCCCACUGAUGCUGUCUCCAAGAAUAUGAAAAAUAAGCAGAUAGUUCCCAGUCCUCACACAGGGGUUAUCAGAGUGGGCUGCCUAUGUUAUCAGAGCCCAGGCCAACCUGGGAACUCAGCUGGAAGGGCUCAUCAGUUAUGGGCUGAAGGCAAAGAACCCCUUGAUGAGGAUCUCCCAAGCCCAUUGCAGGGGUCACAGUCAAAAUUGAUAGAGAAACUUCUAGCCUGUUUCCUUGCCUUUGGAAUUGCGCUGAUACCAGAACCAGACCAUGCUGUCUGUGGGGCCUCAGUGUUUGCUUUUGCUGAAUUUGCUUUGACUGUCAGCAAGUUGGAUUGGAUUUGUGGCUCAGAGUAGGGUAAGAGAAGGCAGCCUGGGUCUUGGUAAUGGCAGGGCAAACUAGUUGGGUGUGUGCAGGCCUCGUCCACGGAUUCAGCCCAGGGCUGGGAGCACUUCCUGCUCUGACAGCCCCCAUGCAGUCAGGCUCCAUAAGGCACACAGAUGACGGAGCCACACAGGGCAGGGGCAGAAUGCAGAGCCGCCCAGCAGCGCACAGCUCAGGCCCACCUACCCUUGCCGAAAUGAGAGGGGGAGGGGGCUGAGAUGGGUACAUCAAGCCCAUCUUAGCUAAGCCUGAGGCACAUACCUUUUGUCCCAGCUCCCCAAGACUGUGCCAUCCCUGCCAUCAGAGCCUCCCAGGCACCUGGUCUGGCUCAUCCACCUAGCCACUCCCCAGAGGAAGGGUAGUCUAUAAGGUGUGAGGACAGUAUCUUGAGUGGUGUGUGCCCAGGAGCCAAGCCUGGGGCCUGGCUCCUCCCAGCCCACCCCCGGGCCUCCUGGUCGUGACCGGCUGUGGCAACAAGCAGUGUAUGUGGGACUCUGGACUGGUUUCUAUUGAAGGGGAGGCUGCCAAGCUGGUGUUCCUCAGGCUGGGACCCCCAUGCCAGGCCACUGCCUCAGGCUCUGACCCCUCUCUCCCCAGCUCUAUAGCAUCGCCGCACCAGCUCGAAGCUUCCGAGAUUUCAAAGUUCAGUUUGUGCCCUUUCAUUCAGACCUUGGCUACAGGCACAAA